ACUGCUCUUCCGGACGCAAUUUUGAGGAGGUCGGAGCGGAAGGACGUCGUGGAGAUUGCUUGCGCUGGGGUGCCACACUUAGGCUGAGCUGCAGGUUUUCGCACAGUCGCGAGUUAACCUCUGCUUGCUCCAGAGGCCUCGUCCUAAUCCACCUCGGCUGACGGCGCGGGAUCCCUGGCUCCGCGAGCCUCAGCCUCACCAUGUGUGUCAGGAGCUGUUUCCAGUCCCCCCGUCUCCAGUGGGUGUGGAGAACAGCCUUCCUGAAACACACCCAGCGCAGGCACCAGGGGUCCCACCGAUGGACACACCUUGGAGGCAGCACCUACAGAGCGGUGAUUUUCGACAUGGGCGGAGUUCUCAUUCCUUCUCCAGGGAGAGUCGCUGCAGAAUGGGAGGUACAGAAUCGUAUCCCUUCUGGAACUAUAUUAAAGGCCUUGAUGGAAGGUGGUGAAAAUGGGCCCUGGAUGAGAUUUAUGAGAGCAGAAAUAACAGCAGAGGGUUUUUUACGAGAAUUUGGGAGACUUUGCUCUGAAAUGUUAAAGACCUCCGUGCCUGUGGACUCAUUUUUCUCUCUGUUGACCAGUGAGCGAGUGGCAAAGCAGUUCCCAGUGAUGACUGAGGCCAUAACUCAAAUUCGGGCAAAAGGUCUUCAGACUGCAGUCUUGAGCAAUAAUUUUUAUCUUCCCAACCAGAAAAGCUUUUUGCCCCUGGACCGGAAACAGUUUGAUGUGAUUGUGGAGUCCUGCAUGGAAGGGAUCUGUAAGCCAGACCCUAGGAUCUACAAGCUGUGCUUGGAGCAGCUCGGCCUGCAGCCCUCUGAGUCCAUCUUUCUUGAUGACCUUGGAACAAAUCUAAAAGAAGCUGCCAGACUUGGUAUUCACACCAUUAAGAGACAGGGUUUUGCCGUGUUGCCCAAGCUGGUGUCGAACUCCUGGGCUCAAGCGAUCUACCCACCUUACCCUCCCAAAGUGGUGAGAUUACAGGUUAAUGACCCAGAGACUGCAGUAAAGGAAUUAGAAGCUCUCUUGGGUUUUACAUUGAGAGUAGGUGUUCCAAACACUCGGCCUGUGAAAAAGACGAUGGAAAUUCCGAAAGAUUCCUUGCAGAAGUACCUCAAAGACUUACUGGGUAUCCAGACCACAGGCCCAUUGGAACUACUUCAGUUUGAUCACGGGCAGUCAAAUCCAACUUACUACAUCAGGCUGGCUAAUCGUGAUCUAGUUCUGAGGAAGAAGCCCCCAGGGACACUCCUUCCAUCUGCCCAUGCCAUAGAGAGGGAGUUCAGGAUUAUGAAAGCCCUUGCAAAUGCUGGAGUACCUGUCCCUAACGUUCUUGAUCUCUGUGAAGAUUCAAGUGUCAUUGGCACCCCCUUCUAUGUGAUGGAGUACUGCCCAGGUCUCAUCUACAAAGACCCUUCCCUGCCAGGCUUGGAGCCCAGCCACAGACGAGCCAUAUACACUGCCAUGAACACAGUCCUGUGCAAAAUUCACAGUGUGGAUCUGCAGGCUGUGGGACUUGAAGACUAUGGGAAGCAAGGGGACUAUAUUCCACGCCAGGUACGAACCUGGGUUAAGCAGUAUCGAGCUUCCGAAACUAGCACCAUCCCAGCCAUGGAGAGGCUGAUCGAAUGGCUGCCCCUCCAUCUUCCCCGUCAGCAGAGGACCACAGUGGUGCACGGGGACUUCAGGCUCGACAACCUGGUGUUUCAUCCAGAAGAGCCAGAGGUGCUUGCUGUCCUUGACUGGGAACUUUCUACCUUGGGCGACCCCCUUGCUGAUGUGGCCUACAGCUGCCUGGCUCAUUACCUGCCAUCCAGUUUUCCCGUGCUGAGAGGUAUUAAUGACUGUGACUUGACACAGCUGGGAAUCCCUGCUGCAGAGGAGUAUUUCAGGAUGUACUGUCUCCAAAUGGGGCUCCCUCCCACUGAGAACUGGAACUUCUAUAUGGCUUUUUCCUUUUUCCGUGUGGCUGCAAUCCUACAGGGAGUCUACAAGCGAUCACUCACAGGGCAAGCAAGCUCCACAUAUGCGGAACAAACUGGAAAGCUGACCGAAUUUGUGUCUAACCUGGCGUGGGAUUUCGCAGUCAAAGAAGGGUUCCGGGUUUUCAAAGAGAUGCCCUUCACAAAUCCGUUAACAAGGUCCUACCACACGUGGGCCAGGCCCCAGUCCCAGUGGUGCCCCACAGGCAGCAGGAGUUAUAGCUCCGUUCCAGAAGCUUCCCCAGCUCAUACCUCAAGGGGAGGUCUGGUUAUCUCUCCAGAGAGCCUCUCUCCACCUGUCAGAGAGCUGUAUCACCGGCUGAAGCACUUCAUGGAGCAACGUGUGUACCCUGCAGAGCCAGAGCUGCAGAGUCACCAGGCCUCAGCAGCCAGGUGGAGCCCCUCCCCACUGAUCGAAGACCUCAAGGAGAAAGCCAAAGCUGAAGGACUUUGGAACCUUUUCCUACCCUUAGAGGCUGAUCCCGAGAAAAAAUACGGAGCAGGACUGACCAAUGUGGAAUAUGCACAUCUGUGUGAGCUCAUGGGCACGUCCCUGUAUGCCCCCGAGGUAUGUAACUGCUCUGCGCCUGACACGGGCAACAUGGAGCUGCUGGUGAGGUAUGGCACCGAAGCGCAGAAGGCUCGCUGGCUGAUUCCUCUGCUGGAGGGGAAAGCCCGCUCCUGUUUUGCUAUGACCGAGCCCCAGGUUGCCUCUUCAGAUGCCACCAACAUUGAGGCUUCCAUCAGAGAGGAGGACAGCUUCUAUGUCAUAAACGGUCACAAAUGGUGGAUCACAGGCAUCCUGGAUCCUCGUUGCCAACUCUGUGUGUUUAUGGGAAAAACAGACCCACAUGCACCAAGACACCGGCAGCAGUCUGUGCUCUUGGUUCCCAUGGAUACCCCAGGGAUAAAAAUCAUCCGGCCUCUGACGGUGUAUGGACUGGAAGAUGCACCAGGUGGCCAUGGUGAAGUCCGAUUUGAGCACGUGCGUGUGCCCAAAGAGAACAUGGUCCUGGGCCCUGGCCGAGGCUUUGAGAUCGCCCAGGGCAGACUGGGCCCCGGCAGGAUCCAUCACUGCAUGAGGCUGAUCGGGUUCUCAGAGAGGGCCCUGGCACUCAUGAAGGCCCGCGUGAAGUCCCGCUUGGCUUUUGGGAAGCCCCUGGUGGAGCAGGGCACAGUGCUGGCGGACAUCGCGCAGUCGCGCGUGGAGAUUGAGCAGGCACGGCUGCUGGUGCUGAGAGCUGCCCACCUCAUGGACCUGGCAGGAAACAAGGCUGCAGCCUUGGAUAUAGCCAUGAUUAAAAUGGUCGCCCCGUCCAUGGCCUCCCGAGUGAUUGAUCGUGCGAUUCAGGCCUUUGGAGCAGCAGGCCUGAGCAGCGACUACCCACUGGCUCAGUUCUUCACCUGGGCCCGAGCCCUGCGCUUUGCCGACGGCCCUGACGAGGUGCACCGGGCCACGGUGGCCAAGCUAGAGCUGAAGCACCGCAUUUAGAGCCUUGGGGCUGCAGUGGCUCAAUGUCCUGGCUGGUCCAGCUGUGCCCAGAUCUGUCACUGAUGUGCCUCGAAAGAUCCGGUGUUUGUGGCUCCUGCACCCUGCUCAGCAGCUCUGUCCCGGGACAGUCAGGGUGGACUCAAUCUUUCUGGUUCUCCACAGAAGACGUCUCUGCAAGAAGCCUGGAGUCUGUUUCAGGCCAGGAGGAGGGGAUUUGCUGAGGGCCAAGGGGGUUCUGGGACAGAGUCUGGAAAGCUGGUCUUCAGGCUCUCAGUCCCAGGCUGGGCAGGCACGGUCACUUCACUUCAGCCUUUCAGUCCCUCUCUCUCUGCCUGUGGGAAUCUGGACACAUUUUGGGAGGCCUCCCAAGGCUGUGGGACGUGCUUGCUCUGGCAGCUGCAGGGUUCCUGUCUGGCCUCCCUGGUGAGCAGAGGGGCGGCCACGGCGGGCGGUGGCCUAGAGACCCAGGACCUGGGCGCCUGGGAAAAUGGAAUGCAACCCACAUUGUAAAGCCACUGGCAUCUGAUUAUCUCCAUUUGAACACACAGCACAGAACAAUCAUUUAAAUGUUAUUUUGGAAAGGGGUUUUGGGGACACAGAAGAAUAAGUAAACACAUCUCGGAGGC